GCGUUCAUUUUCAGCCUGGUGUGGGGUGAGUGGUACCCAACGGGCCGGGGCGCCGCGUCCGCAGGAAGAGGCGCGGGGUGCAGGUCAGCGCCAGCGGGGGCGCGGCGCAUGUGUGGGCCGUGGCGCUGGGCGGCGUGGGGGUGCUGGACGGUGUCCCUGUGCUGGACGGUGUCCCGCUGGCUCAGAACCGGCGCGGGGCCUGGGUCGGGGCCGCCCUCGCUUCCGGCCUCCCAGUCGGGCCCUGUCGCUGGCGUUGGAUUUGACUGACCGCCAGCGUGGUGGCAACGCUGAAGCGUCCAGAAUCUUCUGCCUAACCUCUCGCCGGCAUGGAACUGGCUAGCCGUUUUAUUAAACUCUGUUUUGCGUGGACGGCUUGUAAACAUAUAACAUAAAAAUGGCUUCCAAAAGAGCUCUGGUCAUCCUGGCUAAAGGAGCAGAGGAAAUGGAGACGGUCAUCCCUGUAGAUGUCAUGAGGCGAGCUGGGAUUAAGGUCACCGUUGCAGGCCUGGCUGGAAAAGACCCAGUACAGUGUAGCCGUGAUGUGGUCAUUUGUCCUGAUGCCAGCCUUGAAGAUGCAAAAAAAGAGGGACCAUAUGAUGUGGUGGUUCUACCAGGAGGUAAUCUGGGCGCACAGAAUUUAUCUGAGUCUGCUGCUGUGAAGGAGAUACUGAAGGAGCAGGAAAACCGGAAGGGCCUGAUAGCCGCCAUCUGUGCAGGUCCUACUGCUCUGUUGGCUCAUGAAAUAGGUUUUGGAAGUAAAGUUACAACACACCCUCUUGCUAAAGACAAAAUGAUGAAUGGAGGUCAUUACACCUACUCUGAGAAUCGUGUGGAAAAAGACGGCCUGAUUCUUACAAGCCGGGGGCCUGGGACCAGCUUCGAGUUUGCGCUUGCAAUUGUUGAAGCCCUGAAUGGCAAGGAGGUGGCGGCUCAAGUGAAGGCUCCACUUGUUCUUAAAGACUAGAGCAGCGAACUGCGACGAUCACUUAGAGAAACAGGCCGUUAGGAAUCCAUUCUCACUGUGUUCGCUCUAAACAAAACAGUGGUAGGUUAAUGUGUUCAGAAGUCGCUGUCCUUACUACUUUUGCGGAAGUAUGGAAGUCACAACUACACAGAGAUUUCUCAGCCUACAAAUUGUGUCUAUACAUUUCUAAGCCUUGUUUGCAGAAUAAACAGGGCAUUUAGCAAACUACUGAUUGUUUCUUGUUUUGUCUCUCAUUUCUUUUGUGAAAUUAAAUUCCGUAUCACCUUCAUUUGCAGCUCUUAACUGUCCAUAUGGCACUGAAAUAAAAGAACAGUGACCACAUUUUACACAGCAAGGAGGAAAGGCAUACAAACAGAAUUUAAGAGGCUUGUGAUUUUCUCUGCUUAUUAGCUGUGUGUUUUUAAUGUGCUAUUAAAAAAUACCAAUGAGG